AAUCCAGCAAUACGGCUCCCACAGCACAAGGGGGUGGAGGUUUGGCCCUAAAGCUUCAGGACACCAAAGAAAUUCAGUCGAACAGCCCACCAGUUCUCUCCAUAGGGACCUGGGUCCCGUGAAUGCUGGUUAUCUCACACCCUGAGGAAUAAAGAUUGGAAUCCGCACUGGAUGCUGGAAGUUGACUCGGAGAAAAUUGCGACAGGAGGGAAAUGGCGGCUCUGCAAAAGUUGCCACACUGCAGAAAGCUGGUCCUGCUGUGCUUCCUUUUGGCGACCCUGUGGGAGGCCAGGGCCGGGCAGAUUCGCUAUUCUGUGCGGGAAGAGAUCGACAGAGGCUCCUUCGUAGGCAACAUCGCCAAGGACUUGGGUUUGGAGCCCCUGGCACUGGCAGAGCAGGGAGUCCGCAUCGUCUCCAGAGGUAGGUCCCAGCUCUUUGCUCUGAACCCGCGAAGCGGCAGCUUGGUCACUGCGAACAGGAUAGACCGGGAGGAGCUCUGCGCUCAGAGCGCACCCUGUCUGUUGAAUUUUAACAUUCUGCUGGAGGAUAAAUUGACUAUUUAUUCAGUAGAGGUGGAAAUAACAGAUAUUAACGAUAAUGCCCCUCGCUUUGGAGUAGAGGAACUGGAGCUAAAAAUCAGUGAAACCACUACGCCAGGAUUCCGGAUUCCUCUUAAGAAUGCGCAUGAUGCAGACGUAGGUGAGAACGCCCUUCAGAAGUACGCACUCAACCCAAAUGACCACUUCUCCCUGGACGUGCGAAGGGGAGCUGAUGGGAACAAGUACCCAGAACUGGUGCUGGAGCGCUCUCUGGACCGCGAGGAAGAGGCUGUUCACCACCUCGUUCUCGUGGCUUCUGAUGGGGGUGACCCAGUGCUAUCUGGCACCUCCCGCAUCUGCGUGAAGGUCCUGGAUGCGAACGACAAUGCGCCUGUUUUUACACAGCCCGAGUACCGCAUAAGCAUUCCGGAGAAUACGCUCGUGGGCACCCGGAUACUCACGGUGACCGCCACUGACGCAGAUGAGGGCUACUACGCUCAAGUGGUAUAUUUUCUAGAGAAAAGCCCUGGAGAAACCUCAGAGGUAUUUGAGCUUAAGUCAACAUCUGGAGAACUGACAAUCAUAAAAGAUCUAGAUUAUGAGGAUGCUACAUUCCAUGAAAUUGAUAUUGAAGCUCAGGAUGGUCCGGGCCUUCUAACCAGAGCGAAGGUUAUCGUCACGGUUCUGGAUGUGAAUGACAAUGCCCCAGAAUUUUACAUGACAUCUGCUACUAGCUCAGUUUCUGAAGACUCUCUUCCAGGAACCAUAAUUGGGCUUUUUAAUGUACAUGAUAGAGACUCUGGGCAGAACGCAUUCACCACCUGUUCACUCCCCGAGGAUCUUCCUUUUAAGUUAGAAAAGUCAGUAGACAAUUACUACCGACUGGUUACAACCAGAGCCCUUGACAGGGAACAGUUUUCCUUUUACAACAUCACUCUAACCGCUAAAGAUGGAGGGAACCCCUCCCUGUCCACGGAUGCUCACAUUUUGCUCCAGGUGGCAGACAUCAACGACAACGCACCCGCCUUCUCCCGCACAUCCUACUCCACCUACAUUCCCGAAAACAACCCCAGAGGAGCCUCUGUCUUCUCAGUGACGGCCCAUGACCCCGACAGCAACGACAAUGCUCAUGUAACUUACUCUUUCGCGGAGGACACUGUUCAGGGGGCACCCUUAUCCUCUUACAUCUCUAUCAACUCCGACACUGGAGUACUCUAUGCACUGCGCUCCUUUGAUUAUGAGCAGUUGCGAGACUUGCAAGUGUGGGUGAUAGCGCGGGACAGCGGGAACCCUCCACUCAGUAGCAAUGUAUCAUUAAGCCUGUUCGUGCUGGACCAGAACGACAACGCGCCCGAGAUCCUGUACCCUGCCUUCCCCACAGACGGUUCCACUGGCGUGGAGCUGGCGCCCCGCUCCGCAGAGCCCGGCUACCUGGUGACCAAGGUGGUGGCGGUGGACAGAGACUCGGGCCAGAACGCCUGGCUGUCUUACCACCUGCUCAAGGCCAGCGAGCCGGGACUCUUCUCGGUGGGUCUGCACACGGGCGAGGUGCGCACGGCGCGAGCCCUGCUGGACAGAGACGCGCUCAAGCAGAGCCUCGUGGUGGCCAUCCAGGACCACGGCCAGCCCCCUCUCUCCGCCACUGUCACGCUCACCGUGGCCGUGGCCGACAGGAUCCCCGACAUCCUGGCCGACCUGGGCAGCCUCGAGCCCUCCGCCAUACCCAACGAUUCGGACCUCACUCUGUACCUGGUGGUGGCGGUGGCCGCGGUCUCCUGCGUCUUCCUGGCCUUCGUCAUCGUGUUGCUGGCGCACAGGCUGCGGCGCUGGCACAAGUCACGCCUGCUGCAGGCUUCAGGAGGCAGCUUGACAGGCAUGCAGAGCUCGCACUUUGUGGGCGUGGACGGGGUUCGGGCUUUCCUGCAGACCUAUUCCCACGAGGUCUCCCUCACUGCGGACUCGCGGAAGAGCCACCUGAUUUUCCCCCAGCCCAACUAUGCGGACACGCUCAUCAGCCAGGAGAGCUGUGAGAAAAAGGAUUUUUUAUCAGCGCCUCAAUCUCUACUCGAAGAAGAAAGAGAAGAAACGUUUUCUCAGCAAGCCCCGCCCAACACGGACUGGCGUUUCUCUCAGGCCCAGAGACCCGGCACCAGCGGCUCCCAAAAUGGCGAUGACACCGGCACCUGGCCCAACAACCAGUUUGACACAGAGAUGCUGCAAGCCAUGAUCUUGGCGUCCGCCAGUGAAGCUGCUGAUGGGAGCUCCACCCUGGGAGGGGGUGCCGGCACCAUGGGAUUGAGCGCCCGCUACGGACCCCAGUUCACCCUGCAGCACGUGCCCGACUACCGCCAGAAUGUCUACAUCCCAGGCAGCAAUGCCACACUGACCAACGCAGCUGGCAAGCGGGAUGGCAAGGCCCCAGCAGGUGGCAAUGGCAACAAGAAGAAGUCGGGCAAGAAGGAGAAGAAGUAACAUGGAGGCCAGGCCAAGAGCCACAGGGCGGCCUCUCCCCAACCAGCCCAGCUUCUCCUUACCUGCACCCAGGCCUCAGAGUUUCAGGGCUAACCCCCAGAAUACUGGUAGGGGCCAAGGCCAUGCUCCCCUUGGGAAACAGAAACAAGUGCCCAGUCAGCACCUACCCCUUCCCCCCCAGGGGGUUGAAUAUGCAAAAGCAGUUCCGCUGGGAACCCCCAUCCAAUCAACUGCUGUACCCAUGGGGGUAGUGGGGUUACUGUAGACACCAAGAACCAUUUGCCACACCCCGUUUAGUUACAGCUGAACUCCUCCAUCUUCCAAAUCAAUCAGGCCCAUCCAUCCCAUGCCUCCCUCCUCCCCACCCCACUCCAACAGUUCCUCUUUCCCGAGUAAGGUGGUUGGGGUGUUGAAGUACCAAGUAACCUACAAGCCUCCUAGUUCUGAAAAGUUGGAAGGGCAUCAUGACCUCUUGGCCUCUCCUUUGAUUCUCAAUCUUCCCCCAAAGCAUGGUUUGGUGCCAGCCCCUUCACCUCCUUCCAGAGCCCAAGAUCAAUGCUCAAGUUUUGGAGGACAUGAUCACCAUCCCCAUGGUACUGAUGCUUGCUGGAUUUAGGGAGGGCAUUUUGCUACCAAGCCUCUUCCCAACGCCCUGGGGACCAGUCUUCUGUUUUGUUUUUCAUUGUUUGACGUUUCCACUGCAUGCCUUGACUUCCCCCACCUCCUCCUCAAACAAGAGACUCCACUGCAUGUUCCAAGACAGUAUGGGGUGGUAAGAUAAGGAAGGGAAGUGUGUGGAUGUGGAUGGUGGGGGCAUGGACAAAGCUUGACACAUCAAGUUAUCAAGGCCUUGGAGGAGGCUCUGUAUGUCCUCAGGGGACUGACAACAUCCUCCAGAUUCCAGCCAUAAACCAAUAACUAGGCUGGACCCUUCCCACUACAUAAUAGGGCUCAGCCCAGGCAGCCAGCUUUGGGCUGAGCUAACAGGACCAAUGGAUUAAACUGGCAUUUCAGUCCAAGGAAGCUCGAAGCAGGUUUAGGACCAGGUCCCCUUGAGAGGUCAGAGGGGCCUCUGUGGGUGCUGGGUACUCCAGAGGUGCCACUGGUGGAAGGGUCAGCGGAGCCCCAGCAGGAAGGGUGGGCCAGCCAGGCCAUUCUUAGUCCCUGGGUUGGGGAGGCAGGGAGCUAGGGCAGGGACCAAAUGAACAGAAAGUCUCAGCCCAGGAUGGGGCUUCUUCAACAGGGCCCCUGCCCUCCUGAAGCCUCAGUCCUUCACCUUGCCAGGUGCCGUUUCUCUUCCGUGAAGGCCACUGCCCAGGUCCCCAGUGCGCCCCCUAGUGGCCAUAGCCUGGUUAAAGUUCCCCAGUGCCUCCUUGUGCAUAGACCUUCUUCUCCCACCCCCUUCUGCCCCUGGGUCCCCGGCCAUCCAGCGGGGCUGCCAGAGAACCCCAGACCUGCCCUUACAGUAGUGUAGCGCCCCCUCCCUCUUUCGGCUGGUGUAGAAUAGCCAGUAGUGUAGUGCGGUGUGCUUUUACGUGAUGGCGGGUGGGCAGCGGGCGGCGGGCUCCGCGCAGCCGUCUGUCCUUGAUCUGCCCGCGGCGGCCCGUGUUGUGUUUUGUGCUGUGUCCACGCGCUAAGGCGACCCCCUCCCCCGUACUGACUUCUCCUAUAAGCGCUUCUCUUCGCAUAGUCACGUAGCUCCCACCCCACCCUCUUCCUGUGUCUCACGCAAGUUUUAUACUCUAAUAUUUAUAUGGCUUUUUUUCUUCGACAAAAAAAUAAUAAAACGUUUCUUCUGAAAA